AGGAAGCCGGAAGCCGCAGGGGCCGCCGUCGUCUCCUCCGCGUCCCCGCCCGCCAGCUGCUGUCGGAGGUUGACAGGUCGAGGCGGGGAGGCGGCGGCGGCGGCUGCAGAGCCAGGCGCCCAAGACGGAGACCCCAUGGGGAACGCUCCGAGUCACAGCAGUGAAGACGAAGCGGCAGCUGCCGGUGGCGAGGGCUGGGGCCCACACCAGGACUGGGCCGCGGUCUCGGGCACGACCCCCGGCCCGGGCGUCGCGGCUCCAGCGCUACCACCCGCCGCGGCGCUGCUGGAGCCGGCCAGGCUGCGAGAGGCUGCUGCAGCGUUGCUGCCCACACCCCCCUGCGAGUCGCUGGUGUCGAGGCAUCGCGGCGCGUUGUUUCGCUGGCUGGAAGAGCGGCUGGGCCGCGGCGAAGAGUCUGUCACUCUGGAGCAGUUCCGGGAGCUGCUGGAGGCUCGCGGCGCCGGCUGCUCUAGCGAGCAGUUCGAGGAGGCCUUUGCCCAGUUUGAUGCUGAGGGUGAUGGGACAGUUGAUGCCGAGAACAUGUUGGAGGCCCUCAAGAAUUCCAGUGGAGCUAAUCUUCAGGGGGAGCUGAGCCACAUCAUCAGACAACUACAGGCCUGCUCUCUGGUUCCAGGUUUCACAGACAUAUUUUCAGAGUCGAAGGAGGGCCUUGAUAUUCACUCGUCAAUGAUACUGCGCUUCCUGCACCGCAAUCGGCUCUCCAGCGCGGUGAUGCCCUACCCGAUGCUGGAGCACUGCAAUAACAUGUGCACCAUGCGGUCUUCCGUCCUGAAGGAGUCUCUGGAUCAGCUGGUACAAAAGGAAAAGGAAAGCCCUGGAGAUCUAACUAGAAGUCCAGAGAUGGAUAAACUCAAGUCAGUAGCAAAGUGCUAUGCUUAUAUAGAAACAUCCUCCAACUCGGCAGACAUUGACAAGAUGACAAAUGGAGAAACCUCAUCCUACUGGCAGUCAGAUGGCAGUGCCUGUUCACACUGGAUUCGUUUAAAAAUGAAGCCAGAUGUUGUGCUUAGGCACCUGUCCAUUGCAGUGGCUGCCACUGACCAGAGCUACAUGCCACAGCAGGUGACAGUAGCUGUAGGGAGGAAUGCCAGCGAUCUUCAGGAAGUCCGAGAUGUGCACAUCCCCAGCAAUGUCACUGGCUAUGUGACGCUGCUGGAAAAUGCCAACGUCAGUCAGCUCUAUGUCCAGAUUAACAUAAAGCGUUGUCUUAGCGAUGGCUGCGACACUAGAAUUCAUGGUCUCAGGGCUGUUGGCUUUCAGAGAGUUAAGAAGUCUGGGGUCUCAGUCUCAGAUGCUUCUGCAAUAUGGUAUUGGUCUCUGCUGACAUCUCUGGUGACGGCUUCUAUGGAGACAAAUCCCGCCUUUGUCCAGACAGUGCUGCACAAUACUCAGAAGGCGCUGCGGCACAUGCCUCCACUCUCUCUCUCACCAGGAUCUACAGAUUUCUCAACUUUCCUCUCCCCUAAUGUGCUGGAAGAAGUGGACAGUUUCCUCAUAAGGAUAACUAGCUGCUGUUCUACCCCAGAGGUAGAACUGACUCUUCUGGCUUUUGCUCUCGCAAGAGGAAGUGUUGCCAAAGUCAUGAGCUCUCUAUGCACCAUCACUGACCAUCUGGACACGCAGUAUGAUGCCUCAUCCCUCAUCUUGUCCAUGGCGUCAGUCAGACAGAACCUGCUCCUCAAAUAUGGUAAACCUCUCCAGUUGACUCUUCAGGCAUGUGAUGUCAAAGGAAAAGAAGAUAAGUCUGGACCCGAAAACCUCCUUGUUGAACCGUGGACAAGGGAUGGUUUUCUUACGGAAACUGGAAAAACCAGAGCCAGCACUAUUUUUUCUACCGGAACUGAAUCUGCCUUCCAAGUUACACAGAUAAGAAUUAUGGUUCGACGUGGUGGCAUUGGUGCCCAGUGUGGGUUGGUGUUUGCCUAUAACUCAUCUUCAGAUAAAUUUUGUGCGGAAGAACACUUCAAAAGGUUUGAAAAAUAUGACAAAUGGAAGCUUCAGGAGCUCAGGCAAUUUGUAAAAAGCAGGAUUGGUUGCUCAUCUGAUGACCUUGGAGAGGAUGAUCCUAUUGGCUGGUUUGAACUGGAAGAAGAAUGGGAUGAAGCAGAUGUGAAGCUGCAACAGUGCAGAGUUGCCAAAUAUUUGAUGGUGAAGUUCCUCUGCACCCGUCAGGAGUCAGCAGAGCGCUUGGGAGUGCAAGGCUUGACCAUCAGUGGGUACCUCCGGCCUGCAAGAGCAGAAGCAGAACAGAGCGUCACCUGUGCACACUGCAGAAAGGACACAGAGGAGAGUGUCUGUGGGGCCACGUUGCUCCUCAGGACCCUUCAGUUUAUCCAGCAGCUCGCCCAUGACCUGGUGCAGCAGAAGGAAAGUGGCUUAAAAUAUAAAUCUUUUCUGGACUUCGCGGGUCUUGAUUUGCAGAUCUUCUGGAAUUUUUACAGUAAAUUAAAGCAAAACCCGAGGGAAGAAUGCGUCUCUGCCCAAACCCUGCUUCUGCAGCUACUCCAGAGCUGCUUCUCUGUGCUGCAGGGAGAUGUACUGGCUGCUUCUGAGGAGGAAAAGGCUCCAAUCCAAAGCCCUAAAGGAGUAGAGGCUGCCAAGGAGCUGUACACACACUUGUGUGAUGUGGUGGACAAGGUGGAUGGAGACUCUGUGCCCAUGGAGAUACUAAAACAAGAAGUCAGGAAUACCCUUCUCAAUGGGGCUGCCAUCUUCUUUCCUAAUCGACAGACCCGACGGAACCAUCUCUUCACCAUGAUGAAGAAUGUCACCGAGCAGGAGCACAAGCAGUCCCUGCAGCUCACUUUCCGUUCACUGUGCACGUAUUUUAGUGACAAGGAUCCAGGCGGCCUUCUUCUUUUACCUGAGAAGAACGACCUGGCCAAGAUGAACAUCAGUGAAGUCCUGGCGGUCAUGGACACUCUCGUCUCUGUUGCUGCUCGAGAGUGCGAGCUGUUAAUGCUCAGUGGGGCCCCAGGGGAGGUGGGCUCUGUGCUCUUCUCCCUGUUCUGGUCCGUCCAAGGCAGCCUGCUAUCCUGGUGCUACCUGCAGCUGAAGAGCACGGACUCUGGAGCCAAAGAUCUUGCCGUGGACCUUAUUGAAAAAUAUGUGGGCCAGUUUCUGGCAAGCAUGAGAGCGAUUUUGGAAUCCCUUUUCUCACAGUACAGUGGAAAAACCAUAGUAGAAAGAUUAUGUAACUCAGUGUUUUCAAUGGCAGCUCGUCAACUGGUUAUCUUCCUGCUGGACUUCUGCACUUUAGACAUCCCACACUGCGUGCUCUUGAGAGAGUUCAGCGUCCUCACAGAACUCCUGAAGAAGCUCUGUAGUGGCCCCGAAGGAGGACUGAGGAAGCUGGAUGUUGAGACCUGGCAACAGGAACAGCCUGUGGUGUUACAUACGUGGACGAAGGAAUCUGCCCACAACUAUGAAAAUAAUUGCCAUGAGGUAUCCGUCUUUGUUAGCCCAGGGGCAACCUAUUUUGAAGUGGAAUUCGAUGACAGGUGUGAAACUGAAAAAAGGUAUGAUUAUCUGGAAUUUACCGACGCUAGAGGUCGGAAAACACGCUAUGACACAAAAGUUGGCACUGAUAAAUGGCCCAAGAAAGUGACCUUCAAGGCCGGUCCUCGGUUGCAGUUCCUCUUUCACUCUGACAGCAGUCACAACGAAUGGGGCUACAAAUUCACUGUCACUGCCUGUGGGCUGCCCGAUGUUGCCGUGUCUUGGGGGCUGGAUUUACAGCUCCUCGUCUCCCGGCUGAUGGGACGCCUGGCUUCCCAGUGCAUGGCGCUCAAGUCUGUGCGCCAGUUAGGAAGUAACAUGGUAGUACCUCAGGCAAAAAUGGCAUUAGUCCUAAGCUCCCCACUGUGGAAACCUGUCUUCAGGCAUCAGGUUUGUCCAGAGUUGGAAUUAGAAGCAAGCUGGCCCACUCACCCACACCGGAAUAGUAAGGAGGUUAAGAACAUUCCUGACGACCCCUGCCGCCAUUUUCUUCUUGAUUUUGCCCAGUCAGAGCCUGCUCAGAACUUCUGUGGGCCAUAUUCAGAACUUUUCAAAGGAUUCAUACAGGCAUGUAGAAAACAGGCCCCAAAGACAGAUAUAGUUGCUGGUUCCACUAUUGAUCAAGCUGUGAACGCCACCUUUGCUGCUCUGGUGUAUCGCACUCCAGAUUUAUAUGAGAAGCUGCAAAAAUAUGUCAACAGUGGGGGCAAAAUAGCCCUGAGUGAAGAGUUUGCCCAGGUUUAUUCCUUGGCAGAUGGGAUUCGAAUAUGGAUGUUAGAGAUGAAGCAGAAGUCCCUGAUGAGCCUGGGGAAUGAAGCAGAAGAAAAACAUAGUUCAGAAGCUACUGAGGUGAACCCUGAGAGCCUGGCAAAAGAGUGCAUUGAGAAGAGUCUUCUAUUACUAAAAUUUCUGCCCACGGGCAUAAGUUCAAAAGAAAGCUGCGAAAAGUUGGAGACUGCUGAUGAAACCAGUCAUCUCCAGCCACUCAACAAGCGUCAGAGGACAAGCUCUGUGGUGGAAGAGCAUUUCCAAGCCUCAGUAUCUCCCACUGAAGCCGCACCCCCUGCCACAGGAGACCAGAGUCCUGGCCUGGGCACCCAGCCAAAGCUGCCAUCCAGCAGUGGCCUUCCUGCUGCAGACGUGUCCCCUGCCACAGCUGAAGAGCCCUUGUCACCUUCCACACCCACCCGCCGGCCUCCCUUCACCCGAGGGCGACUCCGGCUGCUCUCCUUUCGAUCCAUGGAGGAGGCCAGACUGGUGCCCACAGUGAAAGAGAAAUACCCUGUGCUGAAGGACGUCAUGGACUUCAUUAAGGAUCAGUCGCUCUCGCACAGGAGUGUUGUGAAGGUUCUUUCCCUGAGGAAAGCCCAGGCCCAGAGCAUCCUGGAAGUCCUGAAGAUAACUCAGCACUGUGCAGAAUCCCUUGGGCAGCCCCACUGCUUCCAUCCACCUUUCAUACUUUUCCUGUUGGAACUUCUGACCUGUCAGAAAGAUUUUACCAAUUAUUUUGGACACCUGGAAGGCUGUGGUGCUGAUCUACACAAAGAAAUUCGAGACACUUACUAUCAACUUGUUCUGUUUUUGGUCAAAGCAGUUAAAGGAUUUAGUAGCCUAAAUGACAGGUCCUUGCUCCCUGCCUUAUCCUGUGUUCAGACAGCCCUGCUUCAUCUUUUGGAUAUGGGCUGGGAACCCAAUGAUCUCGCCUUCUUUGUUGAUAUUCAGUUACCAGAUCUCCUCAUGAAAAUGUCACAGGAGAAUAUAAGUGUCCAUGACAGUGUGAUCAGCCAAUGGAGUGAAGAAGAUGAGCUUGCUGAUGCCAAGCAGAAUUCAGAAUGGAUGGAUGAGUGUCAGGAUGGCAUGUUUGAGGCCUGGUAUGAAAAAAUAGCCCAGGAAGAUCCAGAGAAGCAGAGGAAAAUGCACAUGUUCAUUGCUCGCUACUGUGACCUGUUAAAUGUGGACAUCUCUUGUGAUGGGUGUGAUGAGAUUGCCCCCUGGCAUCGAUACCGCUGUCUGCAGUGCAGCGACAUGGAUCUCUGCAAAACUUGCUUCCUAGGUGGGGUGAAGCCUGAGGGCCACGGAGACGACCAUGAAAUGGUCAACAUGGAGUUUACCUGUGACCACUGCCAGGGUUUGAUCAUAGGCCGGAGGAUGAACUGCAAUGUUUGCGAUGACUUUGAUCUUUGCUACGGAUGCUAUGCAGCGAAGAAAUACUCCUACGGCCAUUUGCCUACCCACAGCAUCACGGCCCACCCAAUGGUAACCAUUCGGAUCAGUGACCGGCAGAGGCUCAUCCAGCCAUAUAUCCAUAACUACUCCUGGCUGCUCUUUGCUGCCCUGGCUCUCUAUAGCGCCCACCUGGCCAGUGCAGAGGAUGUGGAUGGGGAGAAGCUGGACCCCCAGACGCGCAGCAGUGCCACCACCCUGCGGAGCCAGUGCAUGCAGCUCGUCGGGGACUGUCUGAUGAAGGCUCAUCAGGGAAAAGGCCUUAAAGCUCUAGCUUUGCUGGGUGUAUUGCCAGAUGGGGACUCGAGCCUAGAAGAUCAGGCCCUACCAGUCACUGUGCCCACCGGAGCGUCAGAGGAGCAGCUAGAGAAGAAAGCUGUCCAGGGUGCUGAGCUGUCAGAAGCAGGCAAUGGAAAGAGAGCUGUUCAUGAGGAAAUCAGACCUGUAGAUUUCAAGCAGAGAAAUAAGGCAGAUAAAGGUGUAUCAUUAUCGAAGGAUCCUUCAUGCCAGACCCAAAUUUCAGAUUCACCUGCAGAUGCUAGCCCACCUACAGGACUUCCAGAUGCUGAAGAUUCAGAAGUGUCAUCUCAGAAGCCCAUAGAGGAAAAAGCAGUUACUCCAAGCCCUGAGCAAGUGUUUGCUGAGUGUUCCCAGAAGAGGAUUUUGGGAUUACUAGCAGCCAUGUUACCUCCCUUAAAGUCGGGCCCCACGGUUCCCCUGAUAGACCUGGAGCACGUCCUUCCACUCAUGUUUCAGGUUGUCAUCUCAAACGCAGGCCACCUGAAUGAAACCUACCAUCUCACCCUGGGUCUUCUCGGCCAGUUAAUUAUCCGUCUUUUGCCAGCAGAGGUAGACGCCGCAGUGAUCAAAGUCCUCUCAGCCAAACACAACCUGUUUGCUGCAGGGGACAGUUCCAUUGUGCCAGAUGGCUGGAAAACCACCCACCUGCUCUUUAGCCUGGGAGCUGUGUGUCUGGACAGCCGGGUGGGCUUGGACUGGGCGUGCUCCAUGGCAGAGAUCCUGCGGUCACUCAACAGUGCCCCACUGUGGCGUGAUGUCAUUGCCACCUUCACAGACCACUGCAUCAAGCAGCUGCCAUUCCAGCUGAAGCACACCAACAUCUUCACCCUGCUCGUGCUGGUUGGCUUCCCCCAGGUCCUCUGUGUGGGAACCCGCUGCGUUUAUAUGGAUAAUGCCAAUGAACCCCAUAAUGUGAUCAUCUUGAAGCACUUUACUGAGAAGAACAGGGCUGUGAUUGUUGAUGUCAAAACUCGGAAGAGGAAAACAGUGAAGGACUACCAGCUGGUCCAGAAGGGAGGAGGACAAGAGUGUGGUGACUCUCGGGCCCAGCUGAGCCAGUACUCCCAGCACUUUGCCUUUAUCGCCAGUCACCUUCUGCAAAGCAGCAUGGACAGCCAUUGUCCCGAGGCAGUAGAAGCAACUUGGGUCCUGUCCCUGGCCCUGAAAGGAUUGUAUAAAACACUAAAGGCUCACGGUUUUGAGGAGAUCCGUGCUACUUUCCUUCAGACCGAUUUGCUGAAGUUGCUGGUGAAAAAGUGCAGCAAAGGGACUGGCUUUAGUAAAACGUGGCUCCUCCGGGACCUGGAAAUUUUGUCCAUCAUGCUGUACUCCUCAAAAAAGGAGAUCAACGCUUUGGCUGAGCACGGAGACCUAGAGCUGGAUGAGCGAGGGGACCGAGAGGAAGAGGUGGAACGGCCAGUCAGCAGCCCUGGCGACCCAGAGCAGAAAAAGCUGGACCCCCUUGAGGGCCUGGAUGAGCCCACCAGAAUAUGUUUCUUGAUGGCUCAUGAUGCCCUCAAUGCCCCUCUGCACAUUCUCCGGGCCAUAUACGAACUGCAGAUGAAAAAGACCGAUUAUUUCUUCCUGGAGGUUCAGAAGAGGUUUGAUGGUGAUGAGCUCACCACAGAUGAAAGGAUACGGUCCCUGGCUCAGCGGUGGCAGCCCAGUAAGAGUCUGAGGCUGGAAGAACAGAGCGCCAAAGCUGUGGAUACAGACAUGAUUAUCCUGCCAUGCUUGUCCCGGCCUGCACGCUGUGACCAAGCCACUGCUGAAUCGAACCCUGUGACCCAGAAGCUGAUCUCCAGCACAGAGAGCGAACUGCAGCAGAGCUAUGCCAAGCAGCGCCGUAGCAAGAGCGCCGCCCUCCUGCACAAGGAGCUGAACUGCAAGAGUAAGAGGGCUGUCCGGGACUACCUCUUCCGAGUGAACGAGGCCACAGCUGUCCUGUACGCCCGCCACGUGCUUGCAUCCCUGCUCGCCGAGUGGCCUAGCCACGUGCCAGUGAGCGAGGACAUCCUGGAGCUCAGUGGCCCUGCCCAUAUGACCUACAUUUUGGAUAUGUUCAUGCAGCUGGAAGAAAAGCAUGAGUGGGAGAAGAUCCUGCAGAAAGUGCUCCAGGGCUGCCGAGAGGACAUGCUGGGGACCAUGGCCCUGGCUGCAUGCCAGUUCAUGGAGGAGCCAGGAAUGGAGGUGCAAGUGAGGGAGUCGAAACACCCGUAUAACAACAACACCAACUUCGAGGAUAAAGUUCACAUUCCUGGUGCCAUCUACCUCUCAAUCAAAUUCGACUCUCAGUGCAACACAGAGGAGGGCUGUGACGAGUUAGCCAUGUCCAGCAGCAGUGACUUCCAGCAAGACCGACACAGCUUCAGCGGGUCUCAGCAGAAGUGGAAAGAUUUUGAACUUCCAGGAGACACUCUGUAUUACCGCUUCACCUCCGACAUGAGCAACACCGAGUGGGGCUACAGAUUCACCGUGACGGCCGGACACCUGGGGCGGUUCCAGACAGGAUUCGAGAUUUUGAAGCAGAUGUUGUCAGAAGAAAGGGUCGUGCCUCAUCUCCCAUUGGCAAAAAUUUGGGAAUGGCUGGUGGGCGUGGCCUGUCGCCAGACUGGCCAUCAACGAUUAAAAGCCAUCCACUUACUUCUGAGGAUUGUGCGAUGCUGCGGCCACAGUGACCUGUGUGACCUUGCGCUGUUGAAGCCCCUGUGGCAGCUCUUUACCCACAUGGAGUACGGCCUGUUUGAGGACGUGACGCAGCCCGGCAUCCUCCUUCCCCUGCAUCGUGCCCUCACUGAGCUCUUCUUCGUCACCGAGAACCGUGCCCAGGAGCUUGGCGUGCUGCAGGAUUACCUGCUGGCCCUAACCACGGACGACCACCUUCUCCGCUGUGCGGCACAGGCUCUGCAGAACAUUGCUGCCAUCAGCCUGGCCAUCAACUACCCAAACAAGGCCACCCGCCUCUGGAAUGUGGAGUGUUAGCCCUUGGUGGGGCGUGCAUGGGACUAGUUCAUCUGCCACAGGGAUUUUAGAGCAGACAUCUAACCUCAUUCAGGAAAACUCCUGUAGCGCCAGUGCCCAGCUCUCCUUGAGCUGACCACUCCAGUUAGGAUGCCAAGCAGCCACGUCUCCAAGAGCUCCCGUGCGUAGGCUGGACACAAGCACAGGCUGUAGCAUGGUGAAAAUAAGCCAAGCAGUGCAGAAUGCCUCAGAAAGGGUGGGCAGGGGGCCCUUAAGAAGGUUCAGAGACCAGCCUUCUCCAGAGGCUGUCACUGCAGGAGCCGUGGGCCUGGGAAGACUUGGAAGCGGCCUCUCUCAACUGGUUUCUGUCUCCGUGGAGCUGGAACUGCCUGCACUUGCCUUCAGAGGGAGGCACAGUCCACCCAGAUCCACCUUUCCAGCAAGACCCCCAGUGGCUGCCCAGCCUGGGAGCACCUCUUUGCUUUUCACACCAAACCAAAACUGGCGAGAGCCCCUCCUAGCCACCAGUGAUCCCCAAGCAUCCAGUACAGAACCAGGCAUCGAGCUAGCUCCCUGCACGGCCGCACCCUCCCAGAGAACUCCUUGAGGAGAACAAGUGCCCUUGGGGACAGCCGGCAGGCGCCCCUGUACGUCUGCUCAUGCACCAGGCAGCACAGCCGCAGUUCCUCAGUUGUUGUUUUGACAUAUUUCAGUUUCCACCUCACGUUUUUAGAGCAGAACCACACUGUCUCCCUGGAGGGGCUCGAGGGCAUGACCGGGGACUGACCAUUCUGUGAAAGGAGCAGAAUGUGAGGAGCACGCGUGAGCUUAUGUACCGUGAAGAUGAUCAGAGGAUAUCUUAUUUUAAGAGUAAAAACCCACAUAAUUUUAUUUCUGCUUGAUAGUCAUGGUAGUCUGUCAUACCCACCUCUGGGACUCUGCGUGGCUGUUUGGCUGUCACUUGUAGCAAUAACGACAUUAGUUCUAGUCAGUGCUGUUUUACAUUUUUCUUUUGAUGGGUUUAGUCUUGCCCUGGAGUGCCGAUGAUGAUUCUCCCUCCAGAGCCACGCUUGGGAACAUGAAGCAAGUCUGGCGUGUGGGCUGCGUGCCGGCCUUAGUGGGACCCGUGGGGUUGGAGCAUGCCUUUAGGGGCAGUGUCUGGGCCGAAGCACGUCCCACCACACAGUGCCAGAGCCAGAGAAGGGGCCCCACCACCAAGGCCAAGCUUGACCAGGUCAGCAUUGCCAUGGCCCAGUGUGCCCCGUGGCCUCUGAAGAUCCCUCUGUGCAGGGUCUGCAGGGAUCUGGAUUGCAAGGGCCCAAGUCUGCAGGUCUGGAAGCAUCUUCCUAUAAGAGCACUUUCGCCUUCUGGGUCAGGACUCCAAGGUGCAGCGGGCUUCACAGCCCUACAAUUGGGUUCUCAGCUAAGCCCCAGAGUUCUGGUAGAACCAUCCCGGGGCGGGUGGAGGGUGGGAUUUAAGGGAGACGGGAACACAUGGGGCAGGUCCUGGAACUUGGUGGCCUGAGGACUGAGGCCAUUGCCCUGGUGGAAAGGCCUGGCCUGGUUCCUGUGGCUUGGGACCUGAAUAGGCAGGUGCUGCUGGCUCCGUAGAAACCCUUUUCCCAUCUUUUGCUCUUUGCCAAACCUACCUUGCUUUGGGAGCUGCCUGCACCACCCCAGAGAAGGCCCCACCUUCUUCAUCCCUCAGACCCGAGGAGGCCUCCCAGUAAGGAGUUUCCCAAGAGGGGACUCACAGGAAACAAGUCUUAGUGCUUGGGAGGGAGGCCCCGCUGCGUGCUCAGACUCACAGCCAACCUGGAAGGUAGACGAGAUAGCGCCACCCACGCCCCUCCACACCCCAGACUCCGAGUAAAGCGGGCGGUAGGGCCGGAGUCACCUCCCCUAUGGCAGUGGCCGCCGCUGUACUCCAUCCUCCCGUCAGGAAGAUCAGCUGUAAAUAAACGCUGGGCUCCCCAGAGCACCUGUCCGCCCACUGCCCUUGCUGUUCUGGGAUCUUCGCUGCAGUUCACGGGAAACAAGCCUGAGUCCGCUCGCACCCGCGGCUGCUCUCCCGGCUCGGCCCGGCCGCCUCUGUCUCCGGCCACCGGGUGGCGCUGCCGAGCCAGAGCCGCCGCGUCCCGGCGCUUUCCAGGAGCCCCAGGCCCGGAGGAGGCGAAGCCCGCAGAGCAAAGGUGGAAACACGUGCCUACGCUGUAAAGAAAUCCUGUUCCAGAGCAUACCUGUUGUACAAACAGACACUGUUCCUAACGAGAGGAGUGACGUAUUUUCAUCACCGUUUUUAAUUUGUUUUCUUACGGGUUUACGAUUUUGAAUUUUUCUUAUUUGGUUGAAAGAAUUUUGAUUCUAUCAGCCUGAGUGAGUUCAGCCUGUAAAAAGGAUGUUAAGCUGUGGGUAAAAUAUGCAAACGAAAAGAAAUAUAUUGUACAAAUUCUAUAUAAUAAGGUA